UCUCACCAAGGACCGAGGGGCCGUGGGAAACGUCUGACGCCCACUUCACGGAGGAGCAAAUGGAGGCCCAGGCCGUCAUUGUGCACGGACACACCAUAGGCCGUACAGAGCCGGGAGUGGGACCCUCGCAGUGUAUCCCAGAGCCCCCAACCCCCACCAGUGGAGAGCUCCUGCAUCAUGUGAUCGAGCUUGUGCAUAAAUAAAGCAGGAGUUUCUACACAAUCCUGUGUGGUGGAAUCUCGACGGGGUCUCCCUCUUAUCCAGGCUGGAGUGCAGUAGCGCAAUCAUCGCUCUCUGCAGCCUCCACCUCCCAGGCCCAAACCAUCCUCCCGCCUCGGCCUCCGAGUAGCUGGGACCUCAGGCGUGCACCACCACCCGAUUAAUUUUUGUAUUUUUUGUGGAGAUGGGAUACCGACAUGUUGUCCAGUGACCAUCUUUCCACCGUAGAAAAGGACACAAAUGGAGAAGUUCUGUGGGUGUGGUGUUAUCCUUCCACGACAGCCACAUUAAGGAACCUGCUGCUGAGAAAAUGCUGCCUUACAGAUGAAAACAAACUUCUCCAUCCCUUUGUCUUUGGUCAGUACAGAAGAACAUGGUUUUAUAUCACAACAAUUGAAGUUCCAGAUUCUUCCAUUUUGAAAAAGGUGACUCAUUUUUCUAUUGUCCUGACCGCCAAAGAUUUUAACCCAGAGAAGUAUGCUGCCUUCACUAGGAUAUUGUGUAGAAUGUACCUGAAACAUGGGAGCCCAGUUAAAAUGAUGGAGAGUUAUAUUGCAGUUCUCACAAAGGGGAUAUGCCAGAGUGAAGAAAACGGCUCUUUCCUUAGUAAGGAUUUUGAUGCCCGAAAGGCCUACCUGGCUGGCUCCAUCAAAGACAUUGUAUCUCAGUUUGGAAUGGAAACUGUUAUCUUACACACAGCACUGAUGCUAAAGAAAAGAAUUGUGGUGUAUCACCCCAAGAUAGAAGCGGUCCAGGAGUUCACCAGGACUCUGCCUGCCCUGGUGUGGCACCGACAGGACUGGACCAUCCUUCACUCUUACGUGCACCUCAACGCCGAUGAGCUGGAAGCCCUGCAGAUGUGCACAGGUUACGUCGCUGGAUUUGUAGACUUGGAGGUGAGCAACAGACCAGACCUCUAUGAUGUGUUUGUGAAUCUGGCAGAGAGUGAGAUUACCAUUGCUCCCCUUGCAAAAGAGGCCAUGGCAAUGGGCAAACUGCACAAAGAAAUGGGUCAGCUAAUUGUUCAGUCUGCAGAAGAUCCAGAGAAAUCAGAGAGCCACGUUAUACAGGAUAUUGCUCUAAAAACAAGAGAAAUCUUUACCAACCUAGCACCGUUUUCAGAAGUUUCGGCUGAUGGAGAAAAGAGAGUCCUUAAUUUGGAGGCGCUAAAGCAAAAACGAUUUCCACCAGCAACAGAAAACUUCCUUUAUCAUCUAGCAGCAGCCGAACAAAUGCUGAAAAUCUGACUGUGUGACAGAACGUAUCACUGAUGACUGAUAGAAAGCCCUCUUUCACUCUGAUUACCCACUCACUACAUGAAGUCCUGAAAAUAACAGAGAAACUGUUAUAUCUUUUUAAUGAUUUAUUUGCAAGUAUUGAGAUUUGACCUGAAAAACAAUGAAACACAUGAACACACUUCCGAUUUUCUCCUCGCUGAUUAGCUUCCUGCCUGCUGUCAGUGCUGGACGAAGUGCUAUAACUACUUUAUGUAACAUUACAGAACAGCUAGAGGUCCUGGGGUAAGAGAAAAAAAGCACAUCACAACAAAUGUGAAAGCCUUCAUUAUUACACGUUCCAGUUUGUCUCGCUGUGUAGGCAUAAGCUAAUGGUUUAUUUUCAGAAAGCUGCCUGAAACGUUGCUUUGUAUUCUUCUAGGAAGAACUUUAAUUCCUCCUGAGGAACUCUACUUUCUGAGCCAAACUGCUAAUUUUCUGCGGAACUGUCUAGAAGAUCAUUCAAGAGACCCUGCAGUUGCACUUUCUCGUAAAAGUUAAAAAAAAAAAAAAAAAAAAAAGGUUUUUCCCGGCCUUUGAACAUUUUGCCUAUGAGAGUUUUGCAUAUAUUUUAUACUUGAGUAGACAACUUUAAUAAUCCAUAUUUAUACUAUCGCAGAAGUAAGCAUUUGGCAAACGUUCAGCCAUUAGCACUCAUUUAACCCUGUUAGCAAUAUUCUUUUGAAAAAAGUGCCAGUCCUUAUGUGAUAAACUAAGAAGCCCAUUGAAUAUAAAAGUGUGUAGGACUGAAACAGUGACCUUAUAUUAUUGCUAAGGGAAUAUGAGAUUAACUUCCUACAGGGGCCAAAACCAGAGAAAGGCUUCCAGCAACUUCGAUGAAAGUAGUUUGGCCACAUGUCAAGCCAAUUGUUUGUACUAUUUAUGUACCUUUUUCAUAACUGGAAUUGCCAAAUAAGCAUGGAGAUCUAAAUGAUGUACUUGUUAGUGUAUUCAUUCAUAUUGACUGUAAAGGAUUAUUUUUCACUCAGUACUGAUGUCCUUGGAAAUCUUACCUGGAAACAUGUUUGCAAAAAACAUUAUUGGGUCUUUCAUCUUUUUCUUGGUAUUACAUAUUUGUUCAAUAAAAAUUAAACACCCUCCCUUUUUUUUGAGUGAGGGCAGGGAGUACCUGAAAUAAGACAAUGUUUACUAAGGCAAAUAAUUGAAAAUUAAAUCUGCACUUUAUGGAAAUGAGGAAUAUUAACAUCUUUUUUCUCAUUUUUUUGUAUUACUAUAUUAGCUAAUGAUCAAAGUUGUUAAAAUUAUAAAUUUAUGAUGCAGAAAUAAAAUUGAUAUAUUUUGAUAUUCAA